GCUCCGGCUCAGCCGCUGGCACCCCCACCGCCACCACCCUAGUCUCCUAGUCGCCUGCCACCAGCCCCUGAGAGACUGCAGGUCCAGUGAAAAGGAGCAGGAACGGCAGCAGCCCGGCCGCCGACCCGGAAGCUCUUUCACCGCCAACCGCGAGGCUGCAAAGGGUGUGAACCCGGAAGCGAUUUCAUAGCCACGGUAACGGCGGGGUGGAAAGCUAAGGCCUUUGAAGACCUGGGACCCCGUAGUUUCGGGAGAGGGUGAGGGGUGAAUGGUGCUGAGGUGCGAGGAGAGGGAAGGACAGUAAAGAGCAGGUGGGCAGGAGGGUCUCCGACUCCAGAGACCUGAGCUUUUGGGGCGCGGGUGGGAGCGCGGGGGAACCCUCAAGACGGCUUUCUUUUGGCGACUGAGGGUUUUUCUGCCACAGGAAGCUGGGCCGGGCUGCUGUGCCUGGGAGGAGGGAAGGAGGAAUGAGAAAGCGGUGACGGUCCCUGCCCCCCCUCGCCAGGUGACUGUCCCACCCAUUUAGUUGAAUGUAGCGGCCAGAGAGGCACUCGCGGCAGCCCGUACGGGUGGGACCUCUCGGUGUCCUUCGGGAAACAGGAGGAGCAAGUUCGACUCCAGCGAGGGAAAACGGAGGUGGGAGACUGAACCAUCUCCACAUCUAGUUGCCCCAGGUUUUUGGCUUUCAUCGCUUUUUCUACAUGUUUUUAGCCUCACCAGAAGUCUUUCAUCUCGGUGGUCCAACUCAGGAUCUCAGCCUCAUUAUUUUCUUACCCUUCUGGAGUGCAUAUGUGCCUUUACAGUUUCUGUUUGCAAACGCUGUCUAGCAUACUAAGAGGAUGUUAGCAAACCUGUUCCAUGGACACUAAAUGGCAGUUGUACAUCUCCCCUCAUCAGUCAUAGUGACAACCAGAAAUGCCCUCCAUAUUUUCCAGUGAUCCCAGUCUUCAAUGCGUCUGUCUCAUAAUUUGUAAACGUUUAUUAUCUUGAAGUCAUUGUUAAUCUGUGGUGAAAAGUAAUUGCUAAAUAGAAAUUCUGAGAAGAAAAAGGCCUCAUCCUUUUCACAUGAUGUAGGAAGGUCUGUUGCAUGAGCAAUGGGAAAUCCAGAAAACAUAGAAGAUGCAUAUGUUGCUGUUAUUCGUCCAAAGAAUACUGCCAGUCUCAAUUCUCGGGAAUACAGAGCUAAGUCAUAUGAAAUUUUGUUGCAUGAAGUUCCCAUUGAAGGACAGAAAAAAAAGAGAAAGAAAGUUUUAUUGGAAACGAAACUUCAAGGCAACAGUGAAAUAACACAAGGCAUAUUGGAUUACGUAGUAGAAACCACCAAACCAAUUUCUCCUGCAAACCAGGGUAUCAGAGGAAAACGAGUUGUACUAAUGAAAAAAUUUCCUCUGGAUGGAGAGAAGAUGGGCAGAGAAGCAUCAUUAUUUAUUGUUCCAUCAGUUGUCAAAGAUAAUACUAAAUACACAUAUACCCCAGGAUGCCCAAUUUUUUACUGCUUACAAGAUAUUAUGCGAGUCUGUAGUGAAUCCAGUACUCAUUUUGCUACACUUACAGCAAGGAUGUUAAUAGCCUUGGAUAAGUGGUUAGAUGAACGUCAUGCACAAUCUCACUUUAUUCCAGCUUUAUUCCGACCUUCUCCUCUUGAGCGGAUAAAAACUAAUGUCAUAAAUCCUGCAUAUGCUACUGAAUCAGGUCAGACAGAAAACUCACUACAUAUGGGCUAUAGUGCACUAGAAAUAAAGAGUAAAAUGUUAGCCCUAGAGAAAGCAGAUACCUGUAUUUACAACCCUUUGUUUGGAUCAGAUCUUCAGUAUACAAAUCGGGUAGAUAAAGUGGUAAUAAAUCCAUACUUUGGUCUAGGAGCUCCAGACUACUCAAAAAUCCAAAUACCUAAACAGGAAAAAUGGCAGAGAAGCAUGAGCAGUGUCACAGAAGACAAGGAACGACAGUGGGUAGAUGAUUUUCCUCUCCACCGAAGCGCCUGUGAAGGAGAUUCAGAAUUACUAAGCCGUCUUCUCAGUGAAAGAUUUUCAGUCAACCAGUUAGAUAGUGACCACUGGGCACCCAUUCAUUAUGCAUGCUGGUAUGGAAAAGUUGAGGCCACUCGCAUAUUGUUAGAGAAAGGAAAGUGCAAUCCAAACCUUUUAAAUGGACAACUUAGUUCUCCUCUUCAUUUUGCUGCUGGAGGAGGACAUGCUGAAAUAGUACAGAUUCUCCUAAACCACCCAGAAACGGAUAGACAUAUAACAGACCAACAAGGAAGAUCUCCAUUAAAUAUUUGUGAAGAAAACAAACAAAACAACUGGGAAGAAGCUGCAAAAUUGUUGAAGGAAGCAAUUAACAAACCAUAUGAAAAAGUUCGAAUAUACAGAAUGGAUGGGUCAUAUCGUUCUGUUGAAUUGAAGCAUGGAAAUAAUACCACAGUGCAGCAGAUAAUGGAAGGAAUGCGUCUCUCUCAAGAAACUCAGCAAUAUUUCACUAUAUGGAUUUGUUCAGAAAACCUCAGCCUUCAACUCAAACCAUAUCAUAAACCCUUGCAACAUGUUCGUGACUGGCCAGAAAUACUUGCUGAAUUGACUAAUCUGGAUCCUCAAAGGGAAACACCUCAGCUUUUUCUAAGAAGAGAUGUGAGACUUCCCUUGGAAGUUGAAAAACAGAUUGAAGACCCACUAGCUAUUCUUAUUCUCUUUGAUGAAGCCAGAUAUAAUUUAUUGAAGGGCUUUUAUACAGCUCCUGAUGCUAAGCUGAUAACAUUGGCAAGUCUGCUUUUGCAAAUAGUCUAUGGAAAUUAUGAGAGUAAAAAACACAAGCAAGGUUUCCUAAAUGAAGAAAAUCUAAAAUCCAUCGUACCUGUUACCAAACUGAAAAGUAAGGCACCUCACUGGACAAAUCGCAUACUUCAUGAAUACAAGAAUCUCAGUACAAGUGAAGGUGUCAGUAAAGAAAUGCAUCACCUUCAGCGCAUGUUCUUACAGAAUUGCUGGGAAAUUCCUACUUAUGGAGCAGCAUUUUUCACAGGACAGAUAUUUACAAAGGCAAGCCCCAGCAAUCAUAAAGUCAUCCCUGUGUAUGUAGGAGUGAAUAUAAAAGGACUUCAUCUCCUCAACAUGGAAACUAAGGCUUUACUCAUCAGUCUUAAGUAUGGUUGUUUUAUGUGGCAAUUGGGAGAUACUGAUACUUGUUUUCAGAUCCAUAGCAUGGAAAAUAAAAUGAGCUUUAUAGUACAUACAAAACAGGCUGGUCUCGUGGUAAAACUGUUAAUGAAGCUAAAUGGACAGUUAAUGCCCACUGAAAGAAAUUCAUGAAAGAGAAGUAACUGUUACUCAAGCCACCACAUUUUGUAAUGCAGAGUUUUUUUUCCGUGAAAGAUUUCUUAAAAUAUUACUUUUGGCCGAGCAUGGUGGCUCACCCCUGUAAUUCCAGCACUUUGGGAGGCUGGGGCAGGCGGAUCACCUGAAGUCAGAGUUCAAGACCAGCCUGGCCAACAUGGUGAAACCCUGUCUCUACAAAAAUACAAAAAUUAGCUGGGUGUGGUGGCGGGCGCCUAUAAUCCUAGCUACUAGGGAGGCCAAGGUGGGAGAUCGCUUAAACCCAGGAGGUGGAGGUUGUAGUGAGCCAAGAUUGCACCACGGCACGCUAGCCUGGGUGACACAGCAAGACUCCAUCUCAAAAAAAAAAAAAAAUUACUUUCAACAAGGCAUAUAGUCUCUUGUAAUAUAUAUGUAUACUAUUACAUUGUACAGAAUCUGUACUUAUGUUUGGUGUGUAAUAUACCAAUUAGUUUUAUAUAAUAUCCUCAUAAGCUAUUCUAAUUUUUGAGAGAAACACAAAAAGUUAUAGAUUGAUAGUCUGUAUAAUAUUAGACAAAAUAGUAAGCUUUAUAAAAAGUUAUUUUUGGUAAAUGGUAAGGAAUUUGGGGUGGAAUGUGAUGAGAUUAAAAUGUAGCUUUGGUAUAACUUCAUGUGUAUUUCAAAAUAUACUGAACGUCAACAUGAUUUGAAUAAAGAAAAUGUAUUUUCUACUUGAACCACAUAACACUGUUAUUUAAAACAGUUUUCUGCAGUCUAUAAACAUUUCUCAACAUUUUUUUAAAAGUCUUAGUUAAAAUGUAAAUCUGAUAUACAGUAGUGUUUCUCAAAGUAUAGUUCAUGAACUCCUUGCAUCAUAAUUACCUAGAUGCCUCUUAAAAAUGAAGAUUUCAGAGACCCAUUCUAAACAAGGGCAUUCACUCUCUGGAAGUAGCAUGGCCUUGUGAACUUAAAUUUGGUUUUGUUUUUUCUUUUUUGCUGUUAGAAUAAUUUCAGACCCAAUAAGGAAUUUCGAUUAUUAAAGUUGAGAAAUUUCACAAAACUGCCUGGCACACAAGCACACACAUACAUAGACACAUUUUAAGUGAUAAUCUCUUGAUAUUAGAAGUUGCAUUUGUUAAAUACAUGCUGUAUUUUUUAUGAGUUGACUUAAUAGUUUAUGUAUAUUGACUUUGCUUUGUAGGAAGUAAAUCACCAGAUAUCUUAUUGUUUCAUUUAGGAAAGUAGUGAUAUAGAUGAAGAGCCAACUUGAUGAAUGUGCUAUUCAUAAGCUAGAAACUACAGUUUUUCCAAACUAAUAAACUGAUGAAUUCUAAAUAAGUUCAGAGAUAUAGUCAUAUUUAAAGUUGUCCUACAGUUUGCAGAUAAUUUUUAUAUUACUAUUCUUCACAUUAACUUCUGCUUAUUUUUAAUGGUACUAUAUGUAGGCCUUAUUAAAAUUAAGAUUGUAUGGUUAAGUAAAGUUAACAAGAAAGCCUGAUUUAUCUUUAAUUCUGUGCUAGGUACUUUUGAUUCUACAUGAACAAUACCCUUUUCAGUUCCCUUCAUUCUAAUGUCCUCAACUGUUACCAAAUACCCUGUUGACUCCCAAACCUAAGAUUUUAGCCUCAACUUCUUUUCUGAACUUCAAAUCUUAAUUUCCAAGUUAUACUUGUUCUAGGUCCAUCUAAAUGGUCUACAGAGAACUUCAGUUGAAUCAUAGCUGGAAACAGAAUUUAUUUCCUCUAUUUGCUUCAUUCUGUCCUUCCACUAUAUUCCCUAUUU